GCCCAGAGGAAGCCACGGGCGCCCAGGCGGGCAUGAAAGGGCUCUUUGACGGCUGGGUUGCUGGGACAGUAACACAGACGGCCGGCCAGGAGGAAGGACCUUGCCCUGUGCUACAAUCCCAGAGGGCUUCCUGAAGGAGGCAGCCUAGAUCUUUGUCCAGCAGAGCCCAUCUUCAGGGAAUAUUGAGGAUCCCGACCCGUGCACCUGCCCUAGCGGAAGACACUCCUGGCCAAGCCUCCAGAUGUGGCUGUGAGGGGAGUGGGCCCUGGCCAAGAUGGCAGCCCCCGCCCUGCUGCUCCUAGCACUGCUGCUGCCCGUGGGGGCCUGGCCCGGGCUGCCCAGGAGGCCCUGUGUGCACUGCUGCCGCCCGGCCUGGCCCCCUGGACCCUAUGCCCGGGUGAGUGACAGGGACCUGUGGAGGGGGGACCUGUGGAGGGGGCUGCCUCGAGUACGGCCCACUAUAGACAUCGAAAUCCUCAAAGGUGAGAAGGGUGAGGCCGGCGUCCGAGGUCGGGCCGGCAGGAGCGGGAAAGAGGGGCCGCCAGGCGCCCGGGGCCUGCAGGGCCGCAGAGGCCAGAAGGGGCAGGUGGGGCCGCCGGGCGCCGCGUGCCGACGUGCCUACGCCGCCUUCUCCGUGGGCCGGCGCGAGGGCCUGCACAGCUCCGACCACUUCCAGGCGGUGCCCUUCGACACGGAGCUGGUGAACCUGGACGGCGCCUUCGACCUGGCCGCGGGCCGCUUCCUCUGCACGGUGCCCGGCGUCUACUUCCUCAGCCUCAACGUGCACACCUGGAACUACAAGGAGACCUACCUGCACAUCAUGCUGAACCGGCGGCCCGCGGCCGUGCUCUACGCGCAGCCCAGCGAGCGCAGCGUCAUGCAGGCCCAGAGCCUGAUGCUGCUGCUGGCGGCGGGCGACGCCGUCUGGGUGCGCAUGUUCCAGCGCGACCGGGACAACGCCAUCUACGGCGAGCACGGAGACCUCUACAUCACCUUCAGCGGCCACCUGGUCAAGCCGGCCGCCGAGCUGUAGCCGGACAGACGUCCGCCUGUGGGGACUCUGGGAGCCCCGGCUGGCGCGCCCGCCUCUCCACUUCGCCUCACUCCUGUCCUGGGACAGAGGGUGCCCUGCCCUUGGGAGAUGGUGCUCUGAGGCCCGGCCAGAGUCUGCAGAACCCGCGUGUGUGUGCUGGAGCCACUCCCCAGGCAGGCGGGGGAACAAGCGUGGCCCCCAACAGCGCAGGACAGGAGGAGGGGCGGCUACAGGGGCCCGCCAUUUGCUGUGCACACAUGGCCCCUCUGCAGGGAGAGGGGCUCUGUCCCGGCUGCGCCACCCCCACCCACUGCCCAAGCCUGCUGCCUCCCAAGUCGCCCGGCAUCCACCUCUUUCCCUGAGGCUGUCCCUGGGGCCAGGCUGCCCCUCAGCACCCCCAAGUGGCCCCGUACUCAAGUCCCACCUUGUGUGUCUGUGGGGGGGCGGUAGCAGGGCUUCUGGAAGUGUGGUGACAACCAAGGACAGGAGGGGCUGGGGCCGGUGGCCGUGGCUGGUGAACCCUGGCCCUGCUAGAGACAGGAGGGGCACUGGCGCUGGGGCUGGACCCGGAACCUUCCCUCUCCUUCGCCCCACACUGAGGUGGGCGGGGCCUCAGGCUGCACUUUGGCCCAGGGCCUGAGUCUGCUCCUGGCUGGGAUAGCGGGACACACCCAGGGCGCCCGGCAACCGGCAGGGGUCGGAGCCAUCUCCGGGCACUCACGGGGCCUUGGCACAGAGGCUUCCGCCUUAGAGAGAAAGGCGCCCGAACAGGAAGGGGUGGGCCGAGGGGAGAUUGGCAGACCCCAGGCCUCCCACCCCGACCGGGACACCCCCAGCCCUACCCCGUGUGCUGACGGCCGGUGGCGCUAAGAGGUGCCAGGAGAGAAGCCCACAGCCUGGUCCUGGCUGCAGCAGCAGGGCGCCUGGUCAGCACUCUGGGGAGCCUUGUGCUCACUCAGCCCGUUCCCAAGUGAGGACACCCAGUGCCACGCAGGCAGAGCCAGGCUGCAGCCACGUCCCGCCCACCCCACACAGAGCCCGUGUCCCUGCCAGCUCUGCCUGUCGCCUCAGCUUCCCGUGCAGCAGGGGGUGCGCAAAGGCCUCUGUCGGGGACCCCAGAGCAGCUGUGAGGGGCCCUGGGCUUGCAGGUCCCAAGUGGGCACUGCCCAGAGCCGAGCCCUUGGUGUCCAGGCCCCGGAGGACAGCUGCACGGCUCCAGGGGUUCCUGCUUGGGGGGAUCCCCAGGAGGAGCCUGUUGGGGUCAAGUGUGGCAGGUGCUUGAAGAACCAGAGGUGGGGGGUAUGGGCUGCUGGGGGUGGGGGUCCCGGCUGGCCAUGCAGAGGUUCUUGGCCCCGGUGAGAGAGCAGGGCUGGAUGGGAGAUGGGAGCCAGGGGUCCGGACCACCCCAGGGCCAGGGAGGACAUCUCCUCUCGCAGGCUGCCUGUUCUGUGCUGGGGAAGCACCCCAGAAUCCCAGACAACCGUUCCUUUCCCUGGCCCUGGCCCUGGCCCGGCUGCCCUGGGGUCUCCAGCCUCUGUGAUUCCAGUGAGCCUGUGCUGCCAGGGUGGCAGGUGGUCCUGAGGAAGAGAGUCCCGGGAAGACGCCAGCCCCUGCACCAGGGAGCUCAGAAAGUGCCCGUCACCAGGCCCAGCCAAGGACCCAGACGUGACCACAGCAGCCCCGAAGCCAGGCGCUUAUUCCGAGGGACAGGCUGGACCUCCCCGCACAGACGUCGCCGUGGCCUAUAGGUAGUUGCAGCUGCGGAUACUAAGAAGCAGCAGGGGUCAGGCGGGCAGGGGUCGGGCUGCAGCAGGGGUCAGGCGGGCAGGGGUGCAAGGUCUCUUGGAAGCUGGCGGGGGUGUCUAAUGAAUGCCAGUGGCGACCCUGGUUCUCAGAGAACCGGGGUGGGGAGAUGCCUGUGAGAGCCUCAGACAGCAGGACCUGCAUCCCGCCAACCUUCCAGGUUUAUUUGUUUAAAAAACAAUGACUGAGAACUGAAAGUGAGAUAAGAUACGGUCACGAUUCUCUGCCAAGUGAUAAAAGCCUGAGGGACGCUGCCAGUGCCAGGUGGGAGCGGAAAGAGGGAUGCUUGGUAGAGGCCAGAGACACGAAAAGCAGCGACAGCCUCGUGCUGCCCUGGCCACUUAGGAGACAAGGGGGAGCCACCCCAUCAGAACCGCACCGGGCACCCCCGUGGUCGGCCCGUGCUGGCUUUAAUCAUGAGUCAACCGCACAGGAAGGGACUGGGGAACGCGGCUUCCCGCGGGGACAUCCCUGUGACAUUCCAGGCAAGCAUCGGGCUGGGGAGGCAGCUUAUCCCAUGUAACUUUAUCCGUUUAGUGGAAUUCCAGUAAAAAUCCAAUUUUAAAUGUU